GUUCCCACCCCCAGGCUCCGCGUUCCCGCCGGCCCCAGCUCCAGCCCCGCAGCCCACCGGUGGGUACUGAGCCUGAGGUGGGAGAAAGGGGCAUAGCGGCAGACUAGGAGCGGGCAACCCUCGCCCUUUGGUCGAAGCGGAGAGCGGUUAUGAGGGCCAACCUUGGGCUGGGUGGCGCUAGGUUCCCAUCUUCGGGGACUCUUCUCCCCGCUUUCCACAUACACAUAAAAAAUAAGCUUUAGGCCGGGCGCGGUGGCUCACGCCUGGAAUCCUAGCACUGUGGGAGGCCGAGGCGGGUGGAUUGCCUGAGCUCAGGAGUUCGAGACCAUCCUGGGCAACACAGUGAAACCCUGUCUCUACUAAAAUACAAAAAAUUAGCCGGGAGUGGUGCCGUGCGCCUGUAGCUACUUGGGAAGCUGAAGCAGGAGAACUGCUAGAACCCGGGAGGCGGAGGUUGCAGUGAGCCGAGAUCGCGCCACUGCACUCCAGCCUGGGUGACAGAGCGAGACUCGAGACUCCGUCUCUUGAAAACAAAAACAAAAACAAAUUAAGCUUUAGUUGUUCAUAUAAUGGGCAGGGAGAGGAGCAUUUGCCAUCUGAAGCGACAGAAAGGAAAAACUGCACACAAGUCGUCCCCAAAAUUUGAGGCAACCGUGAGAGUGGUGGCCUAGAACUGGCUCCCUGUGUGACUCUAGGCAAGACCCUCUUAUUCCCUGGGCCUCGGUUUCCCCUAUCUGUACCAUUAGAGGGUCGAACCAGACCAGCUUCCAGGUGUUUCUACUCAUACUUUUCUUUCUUUGAGCAUUGUUUUGGCGACUAAAGAUGCCUUGGUCUCCCAGAGUGUAAGACAGAAGUGUGCAGAGGGAGAUUUGGGGAGACGGAGGGAGAUAAGAUAUCAGCAUUUGCAUUAACGGGACCAGGGAAAUAAGGUCCAGUCCACCCGGCUCUGCCCCUGUGACCUUCAGCAAGUCACAGCCCUCUGAGUCCCAGUUUCUUCAUGGAAUAGAACAGUCGGAUAGGUACUGGUGUAUAUCAAGGAAUAUUGCACUGGAGAGUUAAAAGAGAAUUCUCUGCUUUCUGUUUAGGGUGGUUUAGAGUGACUACUGGAUAUCCCAAGGCCUUUGGAAAGCAGAUUGGAAUAGAAAGAAGUGAUGGGAUUCAGACCGAGGCCUGGUUCCAACUGGAACCAACAGGGACAUCCAGAGCCAUAACUGAAUCUGUAGAUUUUCCCAUGUCCUCUCCAGCCUUUCUGGGUCUGGAGCCUGGGAUGAAACAGGGUGACUGCUCUCUAAGGGAUAUGUUGUUGGGCAGGUUAAAAGGGCGCUUAUGUUGUUGGGUCCCUAAAAAGUGUACCACUGGGCCGGGCACGGUGGCUCACACCUGUAAUCCCAGCAUUUUGGGAGGCCAAGGUGGGCGGAUCAACUGAGAUCGGGAGUUCGAGACCAGCCUGACUAAUAUGGAGAAAUCCUGUCUCUACUAAAAACACAAAAUUAGCUGGGCGUGGUGGCAGGCGCCUGUAAUCCCAGCUACUCAGGAAGCUGAGGCUGGAGAAUCGCUUGAACCUGGGAGGUGGAGGUUGUGAUGAGCUGAGAUGGUGCCAUUGCACUCCAGCCUGGGCAACAAGAGAGAAACUCCAUCUCAGAAAAAAAAAAAAAAAAUAGCGUACCACCAAGCCGACUCUUCAUCUUAGUAUUCCAUUCACUCAUUCAACAGUGCAAACAUGCUUAGACAGAGAAGAGAUUAACUUCAGUGGCUUCCCACUAAUUACAGAGAUUAAGAAGUGGCUGCCUGAACUAUUUUCCAAAGGAUACACAUUACAAAUUAUUGAAUAGGGCAGCUAACCAAGAAGAUCCUAUUGGUUUGGGGGGAACACAACUUCCAGCAGCCACAAGGGAUGCUGCUACUCAGGUGCCAACUGAAACAAGCUCCUCCACAGAAGGUUUCGUUUAGGUUUUGUGUCGUGAUGGGGAAACAGCAAAGCAAACUCAAACACAGCACUUAUAAAUACGGCAGGCCUGAUGAAAUUAUAGAAGAGAGAAUUCAAACUAAAGCUUUUCAAGAGUAUAGCCCAGCUCACAUGGAUACCGUCUCUGUCGUGGCUGCUUUGAACUCAGACCUUUGUGUCUCUGGAGGGAAAGAUAAGACAGUUGUGGCCUAUAAUUGGAAAACUGGAAAUGUGGUGAAAAGGUUCAAAGGACAUGAACAUGAGAUCACCAAGGUAGCCUGUAUUCCCAAAUCCAGCCAGUUCUUCAGUGCCUCUCGUGACAGGAUGGUCAUGAUGUGGGACUUGCACGGUUCCUCACAACCAAGGCAGCAAUUGUGUGGCCAUGCCAUGGUGGUCACCGGAUUGGCUGUGAGUCCAGACUCAUCACAGCUGUGCACUGGCUCUCGGGACAACACCCUGCUUCUGUGGGAUGUGGUGACAGGACAGAGUGUGGAAAGAGCAUCUGUCUCCAGGAACGUGGUCACUCACCUGUGCUGGGUCCCCAGAGAACCAUACAUACUACAGACCUCUGAAGAUAAAACCCUCAGAUUAUGGGACAGUCGGGGGCUGCAGGUAGCUCAUAUGUUUCCUGCAAAGCAGCACAUUCAGACCUACUGUGAAGUCAGUGUGGAUGGACACAAGUGUAUCUCCUGCAGCAAUGGCUUUGGAGGAGAAGGCUGUGAAGCCACGUUGUGGGACCUAAGACAGACUCGAAACAGAAUAUGUGAGUAUAAGGGGCAUUUCCAGACUGUCGCAUCCUGCGUCUUUCUACCAAGAGCAUUGGCCUUGAUGCCUUUAAUUGCUACCUCAUCACAUGAUUGCAAGGUGAAGAUUUGGAACCAAGAUACUGGAGCCUGCCUUUUCACCUUGUCUCUGGAUGGAUCAGGACCCUUGACUUCUCUGGCUGUUGGUGACGCCAUCUCCUUAUUGUGUGCAAGUUUUAACAGAGGAAUUCACUUACUCAGAAUGGACCACAGCCAAGGGCUGGAACUGCAGGAAGUGGCAGCAUUCUGAGGCCAAGAGACACUCACUGGACAAUAUCAAACCAUGGCUCCUCCUCAGCAUGGCUUUGUGUCUUUCCCAGUUAUCUUGAGGGGAGUGGGAUGUAGGGCUGGUAUUCUUUGCUUAGGUUCAUUUACAAGAUGUAUCAGUGUUGUAAGUCCAAUAAUUUAAGUCCAGUGAUUCAAAAUCAGGUAUAGAGUCCAGAAACAUGGACUACACAUAAGGUUCUCUAUUUAAGUUAAAUACAAAUGCAACUUUUUAGUGAGCUUUUAGGACUACUCUUCAAAAAAAGUGUAUUGCUCAGAAUGAUGACCUGUAAAUGUAAGAGUGGCAGGCCUCUGUCUGUGAAAGUCAGAACACAGGGCUCGAGCCUCUGGAACUGACCCUUUGCAAGUCUUUACAAAAGAAAAAAGGCAGUGGGGAGAGAGAGUGUUUUGGUUACAUCAGAAAUAAUUGAGAUGGGAAAGAAUAGUGCAGCUCCAUAGAGGAGACGGACUGUAGACAAUGAGAUUAAGCUUCAAUCACUGCUCCUCAGCAAUGUGAAGAAUCAAAGUCAGGGCAAGAAAGCGAAAGCUUGGACUUCUAUUCAAAGUGGCAGCAGAGUGGGAGGGCGGUACCCUUCUAGCCCAGUGCUGCUGAGCUUGUGUGAAAAUCAGACCUGAGAUGGCUUGAAGCAGCCAAGAACCACAUGGGCAUUGCCCAGAAUUACAGGAGUUAGCACACCAGCUCUACAGAUAAGAAAACAUUGAAAUUCAAAGAUUAAGGCCAAAAAUAUCUCACUUGCAAUUUUAAUAUUUUCAUUUGGAUUUAUAUAAAUGAAACAUAUAUAUGUUUUGGAAUGGCCAGAGUGAGGCAAAGGGGAUCCCUGAAAUAACAUUAGAACAUACAGGAAAAACGAGGCAGGCAGAUCACUUUAGGUCAGGAGUUCAAGACCAGCCUGUACGUGCGUGCCUGUAGUCCCAGCUACUCGGGAGGCUGAGAUGGGAGAAUCACUUGAACCUGGGAGGCAGAGUUUGCAGUGAGCUGAGAUUGUGCCACUGCACUCCAGUCUGUGUGACAGAAUGAGACCUUGUCUUGAAAAAAAAAAAAACAAAAAACCACAUACAGGAAAAAAGAGAGGGAUGGAGUCAACUGUGCCCCAGACAUUAAGCCCCCUUCAGUGAGGAGGGGCAAGGUGCUCAGGCCUGCCUGUGUGGCCCCCAGGAGUCAGACCUCAGCCUCAUGCUCACUGGUCCAUUUUCCUCCAGGGAAAAUGGAGUUCUUUCUGCCUUCAGAGAUGCCCACACAUAAGGCACAUGAGGCUGUUGGUGACACCAUCACCAACACUGGAGAUUCCCUUUCUGACAAGUCCCAGCCAAAGAAAGAUUUUGCAUUUGUCUUCUCUGUCCUCUGCUUGUCUCUGAUACCAGUGACUGACAGCCACCUUCCUUCUUCCCUCUCUUGGUGUGAUCAUGGCUAACUGCAGCCUCAAUCACCAGGGCUCAAUCAAUCCUCCCUCCUUAGCCUCCUGAGUAGCUGGGACUGCAGGCAUGCACCACCACACCUGGCUAAUUUUUUGUGUGUUUGUGUGGUCUAAAACUCCUGGGCUCAAGUGAUCCAUCUGCCUCGGCCUCCUUAAGUGUUGAGAUUACAGGUAUGAGCCACCACAUCCAGCUGAGAGUCUGUUCUUAAGCUAGUACAAAGAGUCAGACCCGACUUUGAAUCUCCACUUCUCCAUUUAGCUGGAUGAUCUUGGGCAAGUUAUAAAAUCUGUUUCCUCUUCACUUUAUAACGUGGGUUUCAUGAUCAUACCUCGCCACAGGGCUGUUCUGAAGACUGGACAUAGCUAUUUUAAAUGCCAGGAAAGGCCAGGCGCAGUGGCUCAAACCUGUAAUCCCAGCACUUUGGGAGGCCGAGGCAGGAGGAUCACCUGAGGUCAGGAGUUUGAGACCAGCCUGACCAACAUGGAGAAACCCCGUCUCUACUAAAAAUACAAAAAUUAGCCAGGCGUGGUGGUGCAUGCCUGUAAUCCCAGCUACCUGGGGAGCCUGAGGCGGGAGAAUCGCUUGAACCCAGGAGGCGGAGGUUGCGGUGAGCCGAGAUUGUGCCAUUGCACUCCAGCCUGGGCAACAAGAGCGAAACUCCAUCUCAAUAAAUAAAUAAAUAAGUAAAUGCCAGGAAAGGUGGUGACAAAUGGUAGCCAUAAUUAUUUAUUGUCCUCUCUGUCCAGACUAAAUGUUCCCUUUUCCAUAUUAAACAUUUACCAUUCUGCCGGACGCGUUGGCUCAUGCCUGUAAUCCCAGCACUUUGUGAGGCCUAGGCGGGCAGAUCACAAGGUCAAGAGAUCGAGACCAUCCUGGCCAAUAUGGUGAAACCCCGUCUCUACUAAAAAUACAAAAAUUAGCUGGGUGUGGUGGUGCCCGCCUGUAGUCCCAGCUACUCAGGAGGCUGAGGCAGGAGAAUCGCUUCAACCGGGGAGGCAGAGGUUGCAGUGAGCUGAGAUUGUGCCAUUGCACUCCAGCCUAGGCAACAGAGAGAGACUCUAUCUCAAAAUAAAAUAAAAUAAAAUAAAAUAAAAUAAACGUUUACCAUUCCUUGAUCCUUUUUUUUUUUUUUUUUUUUGAGAUGGAAUCUUGCUCUGUCGCCCAGGCUGGAGUGCAGUGGUGCAAUCUCGGCUCGCUGCAAGCUCCGCCUCCCGGGUUGACGCCAUUCUCCUGCCUCAGCCUCCCGAAUAGCUGGGACUACAGGCGCCCGCCAUCACGCCCGGCUAAUUUUUUUGUGUUUUUAGUAGAGACGGGAUUUCACCGUGUUAGCCAGGAUGGUCUCAAUCUCCUGACCUCGUGAUCCGCCCGCCUAAGUGCUGGGAUUACAGGCGUGAGCCACUGCGCCCGGCCUCCUUCAUCCAUUCUUAGAUCUUAUCCUCUAAACCUUUAGUCAUCGUUUCACUCUCCUUUGAUUCCUUGUUAUGGGUCUUUCAACUCUGGAAAGACAAAGAGAUAGUGGGAGAGGAAGCCCGGUCACUGAGCAUCUACAGAGGGCUAAAUAUAUUUAUUCUCAUUUGUUAUUCCCAAUAUUCUCUGUAUUGUGAUUUCCAUUUCACAGAUGAGGAAGCUGAGGGCUAGAAACAUGCAGUACUUUGCCCAAAGUCACACACAUAUUAAGAAGAGCUGAGGUAUGAAUCUGGGUCUGCCUGACUCAAAGCCCAAACGCUUUCCUUUGCAUCGUGUCACAAAGUCAUAGACCAUGACAUUGUUUGUAUCUUCAAGACCAGUUAUUAACUUUCUGGCUCCAAGGAGAUCCCCUGCCCAAGUGCCUAGGGGCAGUAGACAGCUGUCUCAGGGACAGUCGUAGCAUGUGCUGGAUUAUUAGUGCAGCAGCUGACACUUUUUCCCAGAAGGGAGAGAGGCAGCAAGUCAGAAAGUUCACGGGAAUGAGUUGGGAGGGGGUCCCAGGGAAGGGGGACAGGCUGCCAGGAGAAGGAAAGUACACGGGAGAAAAUAGUGGGGCUCUGAUGAGUUAGUAGGGUUCUGUUACCAAUAAAAUUGUUUCCAUAAACUGUA